CUUCCCUCUAAGCGAUGGCUGAGAGGCGGUGCAUGCAGAUGGGGAGUAAGUUUCCUGAAGGGGAGGGUGGAUGCACGCGCGCAGCCCGGCGCUGCAAAUUUCCACUGGGGAGGGAGAACGGCUGGAUGCGGAGAGUUUGGAGUUGCUUGCGGCGGAGGGCAGGAAGGGGAGCAGGGCUGGGAAAGGGGGCUGGCGGGCGCUAUAUCUGGGAGUAAGUUUCCAGCAUCAGGAGAGCCUGCACGCUUGCUCACUACUCUGCUCGCCCCCCAUCUCACCCCCCAAGCGGAUACUGGUCUUCUCGUCGGAUUGCCCAUGCACUUGUUGCAGAAACAGCCAAGGCCCUGGCUGUGGAGAAUGCUGAAGGAAGAAGACGCAGAAGCAGGACGACCCUGAAAGAUUCAGCCUCUUCAUCCUCAAACAGGUCGCUUCUCGGGAGUUCUUGGUGUUGGAAUAUUUUACAGCAAAGCAGUCGACCAGGCCUCCUCUUCCCACCUGUCCAGCAGCAUGAAAGCAGCAUGAUUGGCCGACCGCAGGAGAAGCCCCCAGAACCAGGCCCCCAACUCAGCCAUCUGCGGAGGUCAAGGUGUGAGCGACGUCUCCUCACCACAGUGCUGUGUGGUCUAUACCUCAGCCAGGGAGAGGAUGUGAAACCCCCCGCCCUGCACAUGAGUGGUACAGGCCAACAGGAACACCUGGCUCCAGCCACGUUCACAGACAUGUCAGCCGUGGAGUAGUGCUGACACUUUUCUCUCAGCUUCUCAGGGUUUCAGUCCUUUUGGGUUUGUUUUAUUUACCUUUUUUAUGGUUUUGUGGCUGGACGUUCACAACCAAGGCAGACAGCAUGGGUGACCAGCAACUGUACAAGACCAACCAUGUGGCCCAUGGUAGUGAGAACCUUUUCUACCAACAGCCACCACUUGGCGUCCACAGCGGGCUGAACCACAACUAUGGGAAUGCAGUUACAGGGGGCGGAAUGGAUGCCCCUCAGGCCUCGCCAAUCUCCCCCCACUUCCCUCAAGAUACACGGGAUGGUCUGGGCUUGCCUGUUGGCUCCAAAAACCUUGGCCAAAUGGAUACCUCGAGGCAGGGAGGGUGGGGAAGUCAUGCAGGGCCUGGAAACCAUGUCCAGCUACGUGGAAACCUGGCCAACUCAAACAUGAUGUGGGGGGCACCAGCCCAGGCUGAGCCCACUGAUGGCUACCAAUACACCUACUCCCAGGCCAGCGAGAUCCGGACCCAGAAGCUUACCAGCGGUGUCUUACACAAGCUGGACUCUUUCACCCAGGUGUUUGCCAACCAAAACCUGCGAAUUCAGGUCAACAAUAUGGCCCAGGUGCUGCACACUCAGUCAGCAGUGAUGGAUGGAGCCCCUGACAGUGCUCUCCGCCAGCUGCUGUCUCAGAAGCCCAUGGAGCCCCCAGCACCGGCUAUCCCUUCCCGCUACCAGCAGGUGCCCCAGCAGCCUCACCCUGGUUUCACUGGUGGGCUGUCCAAACCAGCUCUUCAGGUCGGGCAGCACCCUACCCAAGGGCACCUGUAUUAUGACUACCAGCAGCCUCUGGCUCAGGUGCCAGUGCAGGGAGGACAGCCACUGCAGGCCCCACAGAUGCUGUCACAGCACAUGCAACAGAUGCAGCAGCACCAGUAUUACCCACCGCAGCAACAGCAGCAAGCCGGGCAACAGCGUAUCUCCAUGCAAGAAAUACAGACGCAGCCGCAACAAAUUCGCCCAUCACAGCCACAGCCGCCGCCACAGCAGCAGCAGCCGCAGCAGCUACAGCUGCAGCAGCGGCAGGGUUCAAUGCAGAUACCUCAGUAUUAUCAGCCCCAACCCAUGAUGCAGCACUUGCAAGAGCAGCAGCAGCAACAGAUGCACCUGCAGCCUCCUUCUUAUCACAGGGACCCUCACCAGUAUACCCCAGAGCAGGCACACACUGUCCAGCUGAUUCCCCUGGGCUCCAUGUCCCAGUACUACUACCAGGAGCCCCAGCAGCCCUACAGCCACCCCCUCUACCAGCAGAGCCACCUGUCCCAGCACCAGCAGCGUGAGGACAGUCAGCUGAAGACCUACUCUAGUGACAGACAGGCCCAGGCCAUGCUGAGCUCCCAUGGGGACCUGGGGCCUCCUGACACAGGAAUGGGAGACCCAGCGAGCUCAGAUCUGACCCGGGUCAGCAGCACCCUCCCCCAUCGCCCCCUCCUAUCCCCCAGUGGGAUCCACCUCAACAACAUGGGGCCUCAGCAUCAGCAGCUGUCUCCCAGUGCCAUGUGGCCCCAGAUGCACCUACCUGAUGGGAGAGCCCAGCCAGGGUCCCCUGAGUCAAGUGGCCAACCCAAAGGAGCGUUUGGGGAGCAGUUUGAUGCCAAGAACAAGCUGACAUGCUCCAUCUGCCUGAAGGAGUUCAAGAACCUGCCUGCCCUGAAUGGCCACAUGCGGUCCCACGGGGGAAUGAGGGCCUCCCCCAACCUCAAACAGGAGGAAGGAGAGAAGGUCCUGCCGCCUCAGCCCCAGCCACCACUGCCGCCUCCGCCUCCGCCUCCGCCGCCACCACAGCUCCCUCCCGAGGCAGAAAGCCUCACGCCUAUGGUCAUGCCCGUGUCUGUCCCUGUCAAGCUUCUCCCGCCCAAGCCCAGCUCUCAGGGGUUCACCAACAGCACCGUUGCCGCCCCCUCCGCCAGAGACAAGCCAGCCAGCUCGAUGUCGGACGACGAGAUGCCUGUGCUCGUGAGGAUGACCCUCUCUCCCCCACACUCACCCCAAGGGGCUGCCCCCCGCACGCCUGCUGAAAUCCCCAGGAAGCAUCAGCCGAGUGUGCCCAAAGCCGAGGAGCCCCUCAAGACCGUGCAGGAGAAGAAAAAGUUCCGGCACCGGCCGGAACCUCUCUUCAUCCCGCCGCCGCCCUCCUACAACCCGAACCCCGCUGCCUCCUACUCGGGCGCCACCCUGUACCAGAGCCAGCUGCGCUCCCCGCGCGUCCUCGGGGACCACCUGCUCCUGGACCCCACCCACGAGCUGCCCCCUUACACGCCCCCACCCAUGCUGAGCCCGGUGCGCCAGGGCUCGGGGCUCUUCAGCAAUGUCCUCAUCUCCGGCCACGGCCCUGGCGCCCACCCGCAGCUGCCCCUGACGCCCCUGACGCCCACACCACGGGUGCUGCUGUGUCGCUCCAACAGCAUCGAUGGCAGCAACGUGACGGUCACCCCAGGGCCUGGAGAGCAGACUGUAGAUGUUGAACCACGCAUCAACAUUGGCUUGAGAUUCCAAGCAGAAAUCCCUGAACUCCAAGAUAUCUCUGCCCUGGCCCAGGACACACACAAGGCCACACUGGUAUGGAAGCCCUGGCCAGAACUAGAAAACCAUGACCUCCAGCAAAGAGUGGAGAAUCUUCUGAAUUUGUGCUGUUCCAGUGCAUUGCCAGGUGGAGGGACCAAUUCUGAAUUUGCUUUGCACUCUCUGUUUGAGGCCAAAGGUGAUGUGAUGGUUGCUCUGGAAAUGCUGCUACUGCGGAAGCCUGUCAGGUUAAAAUGUCAUCCUUUAGCAAAUUACCACUAUGCCGGUUCGGACAAGUGGACCUCCCUAGAAAGAAAACUGUUUAACAAAGCACUAGCCACUUACAGCAAAGACUUUAUUUUUGUACAGAAGAUGGUGAAGUCCAAGACGGUGGCUCAGUGCGUGGAGUACUACUACACGUGGAAAAAGAUCAUGCGGCUGGGGCGGAAACACCGGACACGCCUGGCAGAAAUCAUCGACGAUUGUGUGACAAGUGAAGAAGAAGAAGAGUUAGAGGAGGAGGAGGAGGAGGACCCGGAAGAAGAUAGGAAAUCCACAAAAGAAGAAGAGAGUGAGGUGCCGAAGUCCCCGGAGCCACCACCCGUCCCCGUCCUGGCUCCCACGGAGGGGCCGCCCCUGCAGGCCCUGGGCCAGCCCUCAGGCUCCUUCAUCUGUGAAAUGCCCAACUGUGGGGCUGACUGUAGAUGUCAUGUCACUCCCUUUCUUCCCCAGGUGUUCAGCUCCCGACAGGCACUGAAUGGCCAUGCCCGCAUCCACGGGGGCACCAACCAGGUGACCAAGGCCCGAGGUGCCAUCCCCUCUGGGAAGCAGAAGCCUGGUGGCACCCAGAGUGGGUACUGUUCGGUAAAGAGCUCACCCUCUCACAGCACCACCAGCGGCGAGACAGACCCCACCACCAUCUUCCCCUGCAAGGAGUGUGGCAAAGUCUUCUUCAAGAUCAAAAGCCGAAAUGCACACAUGAAAACUCACAGGCAGCAGGAGGAACAACAGAGGCAAAAGGCUCAGAAGGCGGCUUUUGCAGCUGAGAUGGCAGCCACGAUUGAGAGGACUACGGGGCCCGUGGGGGCGCCGGGGCUGCUGCCCCUGGACCAGCUGAGUCUGAUCAAACCCAUCAAGGAUGUGGACAUCCUCGACGACGACGUCGUCCAGCAGUUGGGAGGUGUCAUGGAAGAGGCUGAAGUUGUGGACACCGAUCUUCUCUUGGAUGAUCAAGAUUCAGUCUUGCUUCAGGGUGACGCAGAACUAUAAAGCCCUGUGUGUCACUUAGAGACAGUGAAAACCCACGGCCUCCAUCUUCAUUAAUCAGGAAACCUGGACUGCCUGCUUGUUUUGUAACCCUUUUAAACUACCUGUUUUAAAAGUGGUCAUUUUAUUCAGGUUUAGAAAAAAAAAUCCUAUUUCUUUUCCUUUUAUUUAAAAAAAUUUGUUUUUGUGGGGGGUUGGGGGAAUAAAUAAUUGGCACAACUAUCUUUAAGAGGUGUUUCAUCUGGGCUACCUUCUCAUGAAAUCAUUCCCAGUAGGGACUGAAGCUGACCUUCAUGUUCCAUUGCAUUCAGAUGUCAACCAUCCCGGUUGCCUUUUAUCCCAAAGCUUGCUGUGAGUGUGUGUGUGUGAGACGCAGGCGACCCUCUUAGUACUGGGGUCUUGGGGCCAACUUUUCCCAUCAAGCGUUACUUUGAUUCUGUUCUGACCUCAUUCCAUAGUUUGCAGUGAGCAUGGCAUCUUUGCCUGGAGAUACUAUGCUAGGGGCAGCUUUCCAGGGGCAAAGCAAGCCCUCGUGUUACACGGCUCUCCUCCAGCUCACACGACAUGUGAGGAGAUGACCAAAUGUGAAAACAGGUUUCCCCUGUGUUGCCCGUCAUCCUUUGGCCCGUUCACAGGAAUGGAGUACUGUAUAAUUUUAGGCUUUCAUUCCCAGCAGUGUUUACUGAGGACCUGGUUUUCUAGAACAGGUGUGUCCUGUCCUCUUCCAUGUUCCCUGGGGGCUGGUCAGCUCCAAGUUGUGGGUGGCAGAGCUGUGUUUCAGCAUGAACUGACUAGAGACCCAUCUGGAGGCAAAUAUUAAGUUGCCAGGACUGCUUUCACUUCAGGGUGAUUGAAGGACACAUAUUGAAGUACCUAGAAUGCCAGAAAGUGUUCUAUUGCCCAAAAAACAAAUCAGAAAAGCCUAUUCUUUUUUGCAACGCUGUUAAUGAUUAGUGGAGUUCUGAAAUUACUUUGUGCCACUUGGAAGUACUGUGAAACCGCAUUCACUGGGAUUUUGCUGUAAUUCACAUCCGCUGGACUGAAGUUUACCUUGAUGUUAGCUAUAAGAAAUAGUUUUCUAACACAUACGAUAGCAAAUACAAGACAAAUAGCAUUGAAGGCCAACAAAAAUGGCUUCAGAUACACCUUAGCUAUAAUGUUUGCAUUCAAACAAUGAAUGUAUUCAUCACAAGUCACUUACCAAAGCACUUCUAGACUUCUCCAACCUCCAUGACUUUGCUCUGCUUCCUCCUGUCCCUGUCAGCAGGGUUGCUGUUUGUACUUGAAGGUAAUAAACCUGUAAUCCUUCAAAAAUGCCAUUUAGCCCCAGGCUUCUGAGCUGAGUCAGACUGACCCAUCCCACCGUUAGGGCAAAAGUCAGGCUGGGACACAGCGCCAGUACAGAGAGGAUCCUGCUUCAUGCAACUCCCCUUUUGGAGUUAAUGCAGCGUGAUUUCCUGGGCCGGUGUUUUCAGGCAUCGCCCACCCCAGGUAUGCUGGUUCCCAGCUCCACGUAGGUGUGCCUAUCACGCUGGGCCACUUUGCUGACAACAUUCAUAGCUUGACAUGAGAGAGAAUAUCAGCAGAAGCAUGAGAGUAGGACCUGACGUCUUUGACUCUGCAAAAGCAUUUAGCACACACUCAUGGGGGGGAACUGGCUGUGAGCCACAGCAGCCCCACACAGACAGUGGUCUCUGAACUUCAGGAAAGCCAUGGACAGAAAAAAAAAUAAAAUUCUUUUCCAUCAUUCUAUUUUCAAAGAGGUCUUGGCGUUUUCCUACAUCUUUUGUUUAGAGGGGGAAAAAAGUUUCAUUUGCUGCCAUUUCAGAAAGGUUAUGCUAUCCUGUUUUAUCCAAGCAGUUGUGAGUCAGGAACUGCCUGGGCAGUGUGCAUCAACUUUGUGGCCGAACCAUUACAGCUGUCAUAUCCUUGGCUGAUCGUCUCUCCCAGGGACUACUGCCCUCCACUUAGUGUCUGAGGGUAAGCCUAGAAGGGUGCUGCUAUUGGGUCUAUGGAAGCUUAUCUAUCAAAGGAGCAAACAUCCAGAAAAGUGUUUAUAAAGCAAAUGUAUUGCCUCUGUUUAGAGAUUUGCCCAGCUGUUCCAGUUUUAAACAUUAAAAAAUAAACUCAGUUGCCAUGGCAAAAAUAGAAUGCACAGCUUACUUAUAAUUUUCCAUGCAGUAUAGCAUAAGGAUUUUUGACUUGAAACAACCAAAGAACUCCUCCUUAACGAGACAGUUCAAAUUCCUGAAUUAGUAUUUCUUGACUAUCAACUUAAAGAAUGGACUUCCUAGUACAAUGUUGCACUUAUUUUUUUUUCUGAAAUAAUUCUGCCUGCAUGUAUGUGUUGUGUUUUAGCUUCUCCCCUUACCCCACCCCAAAGAUCUUUUCUUCCUAAUGGUUAAUGUCUCAACUCGGUUACUGUUUACUAUCAGAUGGUUUUUCAUUAGUGAAUUUAGACCUCUUUGAGAAAGCUUGUAUAUAAAAAGUUAACAGAUAUAUUUUAUGGAAAAACCCAUCUUAUUUUCAAAUAUAUUUAACUGCUGUUAUAUUUUAUUAGAGGAAGGUUGUAAAUAUUUUCUAGGAGUUCUAUUGUAAAGAAAAGUAUUUUUGAAAAAAAUUAAUGUAAUAAAAAGGAAAACAUUUUUAAAUAGUGGUUGUGAUUGCUUCCUGUUCUGGCUUCGUUAUGUUCUAUUCUCAGCAGAUGAAUUGCAUGCCUUCCAUAUCAGGAUGUAAUUUAUUCAGGUUUGCACUAUUAUAAGUUGACAUCAUAAUAUCUAGUGUGCUUAACUGUAUUUUCCCGGAAUGCAAGUCCCUUGGUCCAUAUUAAAGCACUAUGUAUAGCAUAUUCAUAAUUUUUCUUUUGUAACGUGUGUAUUUUUAAUAAGGAUUUUAUGUAACAUUUUGGCAACAAGAGGACCGUAUUUUCUAGUGAAUUUUAUAAUAACAUUUUGCUAAAAAUGUUUCUUCCUAGGUCAGUUUUUGUUAAGGUGAACCAAAAGUCUUAUUUUACCAGGGGUUUAAAAAAAGUUUGAAGCUUGAAAGCAAAGUUAUAUUUAAACAUCAUAUGUAACAAAUAAAUAAAGAUGUUUUAUAGACUUGUCCUAAAAAGGUGCAUUCCUUAAAAAAAAAAAAAAGAAAAAAAAAGGAAACUGGGGCAUUCUAGGUUGUUUCCCCUCCAAGUGAUAAGCUUUUUUUUUUUCUUAAUUAUCACAAUGCUUCUUCAAAAAGGGAACCAGGGAAAUUUUAUUUAACACAUUCUAAUCAUUAGCCUCUCAGAAAGUUAUUACAGUUCCUAUAGAUGGGCAUUCAUCAAAUGGAGAUGUAACCAAACAGACACUGUCAUAUUUAUUUGUGAAAACCUGAUUCAAUAUUGCAUCAGCUGCUCUGAAAAUAAAAUAUUAAUCUUUUGCGUUU